AGAGCUGGAGCCGGAGCCAAGGGAGUCCAGGCUGCCGGGGGCUGCAGACAUGGAGGGCCAGAGCAGCAGGGGCAGCAGGAGGCCAGGGACCCGGGCUGGCCUGGGUUCCCUGCCCAUGCCCCAGGGUGUUGCCCAAACUGGGGCACCCUCCAAGGUAGGGGAGAAAGUGGAGGAUGUAAGAGGGCACAACCUGGGCACAGAGAGAUGUGACACCAGGAUCAACUUAGAAUCCUGGACUUGCUCUGAAUGCUAGAUUCACACUUGACAGAGAAACUGAGGCGCUGGGCAGAGAGGUACUUGCCUAAGGUCACACAGAGCUGGGCUUUGAAUCUACACAGCCAGUCUCAGCUCCCAGCUCUUGCUCCUGAGUGGAGCUCUGGGAAUGGGUGGACUCAAGUUUUCAGCUCCCAGCAAAGAAGAACGCAGCCCUAGGACCCUCGGAACCAAGGUUGGCUCUGGCACCUGUAGGGCCACGGGCAGCUAUGUCAGCUUCCUCGGAAGGACCGAGGCUGGCUCUGGCAUCUCCCCGACCAAUCCUGGCUCCACUGUGUACCCCUGAAGGGCAGAAAACAGCUACUGCCCACCGCAGCUCCAGCCUGGCCCCAACAUCUGUGGGCCAGCUGGUGAUGUCUGCCUCAGCUGGACCAAAGCCUCCCCCAGCGACCACAGGCUCAGUUCUGGCUCCGACGUCCCUGGGGCUGGUGAUGCCUGCCUCAGCAGGGCCAAGAUCUCCCCCAGUCACCCUGGGGCCCAAUCUGGCCCCAACCUCCAGAGACCAGAAGCAGGAGCCACCUGCCUCCGUGGGACCCAAGCCAACACUGGCAGCCUCUGGCCUGAGCCUGGCCCUGGCUUCUGAGGAGCAGCCCCCAGAACUCCCCUCCACCCCUUCCCCGGUGCCCAGUCCAGUUCUGUCUCCAACUCAGGAACAGGCCCUGGCUCCAGCAUCCACGGCAUCAGGCGCAGCCUCUGUGGGACAGACAUCAGCUAGAAAGAGGGAUGCCCCAGCCCCUAGACCUCUCCCUGCUUCUGAGGGGCAUCUCCAGCCUCCAGCUCAGACAUCUGGUCCUACAGGCUCCCCACCCUGCAUCCAAACCUCCCCAGACCCUCGGCUCUCCCCCUCCUUCCGAGCCCGGCCUGAGGCCCUCCACAGCAGCCCUGAGGAUCCUGUUUUGCCACGGCCACCCCAGACCUUGCCCUUGGAUGUGGGCCAGGGUCCUUCAGAGCCUGGCACUCACUCCCCUGGACUUCUGUCCCCCACCUUCCGGCCUGGGGCCCCCUCAGGCCAGACUGUGCCCCCACCUCUGCCCAAGCCACCCCGAUCACCCAGCCGUUCCCCAAGCCACUCCCCGAAUCGCUCUCCCUGUGUUCCCCCAGCCCCUGACAUGGCCCUCCCAAGGCUUGGCACACAGAGUACAGGGCCUGGCAGGUGCCUGAGCCCCAACCUUCAGGCCCAAGAAGCCCCAGCCCCAGUCACCACCUCCUCUUCUACAUCCACCCUGUCAUCCUCCCCUUGGUCAGCUCAGCCUACCUGGAAGAGCGACCCCGGCUUCCGGAUCACUGUGGUCACAUGGAACGUGGGCACUGCCAUGCCCCCAGACGAUGUCACAUCCCUCCUCCACCUGGGCGGUGGUGACGACAGCGACGGCGCAGACAUGAUCGCCAUAGGGUUGCAGGAAGUGAACUCCAUGCUCAACAAGCGACUCAAGGACGCCCUCUUCACGGACCAGUGGAGUGAGCUGUUCAUGGAUGCGCUAGGGCCCUUCAACUUCGUGCUGGUGAGUUCGGUGAGGAUGCAGGGUGUCAUCCUGCUGCUGUUCGCCAAGUACUACCACCUGCCCUUCCUGCGAGACGUGCAGACCGACUGCACGCGCACUGGCCUGGGCGGCUACUGGGGUAACAAGGGUGGCGUGAGCGUGCGCCUGGCGGCCUUCGGGCACAUGCUCUGCUUCCUGAACUGCCACUUGCCUGCGCAUAUGGACAAGGCGGAGCAGCGCAAAGACAACUUCCAGACCAUCCUCAGCCUCCAGCAGUUCCAAGGGCCGGGCGCACAGGGCAUCCUGGAUCAUGACCUCGUGUUCUGGUUCGGGGACCUGAACUUCCGCAUUGAGAGCUAUGACCUGCACUUUGUCAAGUUUGCCAUCGACAGUGACCAGCUCCAUCAGCUCUGGGAGAAGGACCAGCUCAACAUGGCCAAGAACACCUGGCCCAUUCUGAAGGGCUUUCAGGAGGGGCCCCUCAACUUCGCUCCCACCUUCAAGUUUGAUGUGGGUACCAACAAAUACGAUACCAGUGCCAAGAAACGGAAGCCAGCUUGGACAGACCGUAUCCUAUGGAAGGUCAAGGCUCCAGGUGGGGGUCCCAGCCCCUCAGGACGGAAGAGCCACCGACUCCAGGUGACGCAGCACAGCUACCGCAGCCACAUGGAAUACACAGUCAGCGACCACAAGCCUGUGGCUGCCCAGUUCCUCCUGCAGUUUGCCUUCAGGGACGACAUGCCACUGGUGCGGCUGGAGGUGGCAGAUGAGUGGGUGCGGCCCGAGCAGGCGGUGGUGAGGUACCGCAUGGAAACAGUGUUCGCCCGCAGCUCCUGGGACUGGAUCGGCUUAUACCGGGUGGGUUUCCGCCAUUGCAAGGACUAUGUGGCUUAUGUCUGGGCCAAACAUGAAGAUGUGGAUGGGAAUACCUACCAGGUAACAUUCAGUGAGGAAUCACUGCCCAAGGGCCAUGGAGACUUCAUCCUGGGCUACUAUAGUCACAACCACAGCAUCCUCAUCGGCAUCACUGAACCCUUCCAGAUCUCGCUGCCUUCCUCGGAGUUGGCCAGCAGCAGCACAGACAGCUCAGGCACCAGCUCAGAGGGAGAGGAUGACAGCACACUGGAGCUCCUUGCACCCAAGUCCCGCAGCCCCAGUCCUGGCAAGUCCAAGCGACACCGCAGCCGCAGCCCGGGACUGGCCAGGUUCCCUGGGCUUGCCCUACGGCCCUCAUCCCGUGAACGCCGUGGUGCCAGCCGUAGCCCCUCACCCCAGAGCCGCCGCCUGUCCCGAGUGGCUCCUGACAGGAGCAGUAAUGGCAGCAGCCGGGGCAGUAGUGAAGAGGGGCCCUCUGGGUUGCCUGGCCCCUGGGCCUUCCCACCAGCUGUGCCUCGAAGCCUGGGCCUGUUGCCCGCCUUGCGCCUAGAGACUGUAGACCCUGGUGGUGGUGGCUCCUGGGGACCUGAUCGGGAGGCCCUGGCGCCCAACAGCCUGUCUCCUAGUCCCCAGGGCCAUCGGGGGCUGGAGGAAGGGGGCCUGGGGCCCUGAGGGUGGGGUAGGCAGAUGGGCCAAGGUGACCACCAUUCUGCCUCAAUCUUUUGCAAGCCCACCUGCCUCUCUCCUGCUGCUCCUCCAGCUGUAUCUGCACCUGCCUCUCUGUCCUGGCCAGGGGUGGACAACUGGGGUCCCCCAAAACUCAGUCCUGGCACCUCAACUGUGACAAUCAGCAAAGCCCCACCCAGGCCCCCAUCUGGGAUGAUGGGAGAGCUCUGGCAGAUGUCCCAAUCCUGGAGGUCAUCCAUUAGGAAUUAAAUUCUCCAGCCUCA